GGCUCCACUGGACAUCUGGGUAGGAGGGGUCUCUGGGUCAGUGGCUGGAGAGUCGCCCCAGUGAGUCGGUGUCUAACUGGCCAUUUAGUGGGGCCCAUUUACUGCAGAGCCACAGCUGGUGAGGACAGACGCCAGCCUAACAGCAGCUUCUGUACAACUAGAGCUCAGAAAACCCGAGAGAUCCGUGGAGAAAGAGAAGCCCAGGAGGAGGAAAGGGCUCCAAGGAGCCCUGCUCCUGAAGGGUCCCUCAGGCACUGGUGGAGACCUGUCGCUUCGUAGCAAGGUCCCCAGCAGGAGGACAGAGAUUUGAAAUUGUGGACGUGCAUUAGGAGAGUUACUUCAAGAGUAUACUUCAAGAGCAGCCGUGGUCUGUGGGUGUUUGCAUGGCAUGUGCCGUCAGUUUUCUAAUUCCAUCAGGAUCAACUCCAGUUUCUCAGAAAGCACAGAGAUUGAUUCUUUAGGUGCUGUAUUUUCAAUUCCCUAAGAUGGGAAUAAAUGGAAAUGAAGAGGCUGUGACUGGCCUGGGCAGUCAUCUCCUACAGGUCCUCCACCAUGUGAAUGCCAACAUGGCCAGGUCAUUAGAGCUGAGGGAAAACUAGUGCCCAAAGAUAUGAAAAGAGUGUGGAUCUUCUGGAGAAGUGCUGUUGUUCAACAGGUACAAAAUUGGAAAUGUUGGCUUCACCAGAACCUAAGGGCCUUGUUCCCUUCACUAAAGAGUCUUUUGAACUUAUAAAACAGCAUAUUGCUAAAACACAUAAUGAAGACCAUGAAGAAGAAGACUUAAAGCCAACUCCUGAUUUGGAAGUUGGCAAAAAGCUUCCAUUUAUUUAUGGAAACCUUUCUCAAGGAAUGGUGUCAGAGCCCUUGGAAGAUGUGGACCCAUAUUACUACAAGAAAAAAAAUACUUUCAUAGUAUUAAAUAAAAAUAGAACAAUCUUCAGAUUCAAUGCGGCUUCCAUCUUGUGUACAUUGUCUCCUUUCAAUUGUAUUAGAAGAACAACUAUCAAGGUUUUGGUACAUCCCUUUUUCCAACUGUUUAUUCUAAUUAGUGUCCUGAUUGAUUGCGUAUUCAUGUCCCUGACUAAUUUGCCAAAAUGGAGACCAGUAUUAGAGAAUACUUUGCUUGGAAUUUACACAUUUGAAAUACUUGUAAAACUCUUUGCAAGAGGUGUCUGGGCAGGAUCAUUUUCCUUCCUCGGUGAUCCAUGGAACUGGCUCGAUUUCAGCGUAACUGUGUUUGAGGUUAUUAUAAGAUACUCACCUCUGGACUUCAUUCCAACGCUUCAAACUGCAAGAACUUUGAGAAUUUUAAAAAUUAUUCCUUUAAAUCAAGGUCUGAAAUCCCUUGUAGGGGUCCUGAUCCACUGCUUGAAGCAGCUUAUUGGUGUCAUUAUCCUAACUCUGUUUUUUCUGAGCAUAUUUUCUCUAAUUGGGAUGGGGCUCUUCAUGGGCAACUUGAAACAUAAAUGUUUUCGAUGGCCCCAAGAGAAUGAAAAUGAAACCCUGCACAACAGAACUGGAAACCCAUAUUAUAUUCGAGAAACAGAAAACUUUUAUUAUUUGGAAGGAGAAAGAUAUGCUCUCCUUUGUGGCAACAGGACAGAUGCUGGUCAGUGUCCUGAAGGAUAUGUGUGUGUAAAAGCUGGCAUAAAUCCUGAUCAAGGCUUCACAAAUUUUGACAGUUUUGGCUGGGCCUUAUUUGCCCUAUUUCGGUUAAUGGCUCAGGAUUACCCUGAAGUACUUUAUCACCAGAUACUUUAUGCUUCUGGGAAGGUCUACAUGAUAUUUUUUGUGGUGGUAAGUUUUUUGUUUUCCUUUUAUAUGGCAAGUUUGUUCUUAGGCAUACUUGCCAUGGCCUAUGAAGAAGAAAAGCAGAGAGUUGGUGAAAUAUCUAAGAAGAUUGAACCAAAAUUUCAACAGACUGGAAAAGAACUUCAAGAAGGAAAUGAAACAGAUGAGGCCAAGACCAUACAAAUAGAAAUGAAGAAAAGGUCACCAAUUUCCACAGACACAUCAUUGGAUGUGUUGGAAGAUGCUACUCUCAGACAUAAGGAAGAACUUGAAAAAUCCAAGAAGAUAUGCCCAUUAUACUGGUAUAAGUUUGCUAAAACUUUCUUGAUCUGGAAUUGUUCUCCCUGUUGGUUAAAAUUGAAAGAGUUUGUCCAUAGGAUUAUAAUGGCACCAUUUACUGAUCUUUUCCUUAUCAUAUGCAUAAUUUUAAACGUAUGUUUUCUGACCUUGGAGCAUUAUCCAAUGAGUAAACAAACUAACACUCUUCUCAACAUUGGAAACCUGGUUUUCAUUGGAAUUUUCACAGCAGAAAUGAUUUUUAAAAUAAUUGCAAUGCAUCCAUAUGGGUAUUUCCAAGUAGGUUGGAACAUUUUUGAUAGCAUGAUAGUGUUCCAUGGUUUAAUAGAACUUUGUCUAGCAAAUGUUGCAGGAAUGGCUCUUCUUCGAUUAUUCAGGAUGUUAAGAAUUUUCAAGUUGGGAAAGUAUUGGCCAACAUUCCAGAUUUUGAUGUGGUCUCUUAGUAACUCAUGGGUGGCCCUGAAAGACUUGGUCCUGUUGUUGUUCACAUUCAUCUUCUUUUCUGCUGCAUUCGGCAUGAAGCUGUUUGGUAAGAAUUAUGAAGAAUUUGUCUGCCACAUAGACAAAGACUGUCAACUCCCACGCUGGCACAUGCAUGACUUUUUCCACUCCUUCCUGAAUGUGUUCCGAAUUCUCUGUGGAGAGUGGGUAGAGACCUUGUGGGACUGUAUGGAGGUUGCAGGCCAAUCCUGGUGUAUUCCUUUUUACCUGAUGGUCAUUUUAAUUGGAAAUUUACUGGUACUUUACCUGUUUCUGGCAUUGGUGAGCUCAUUUAGUUCAUGCAAGGAUGUAACAGCUGAAGAGAAUAAUGAAGCAAAAAAUCUCCAGCUUGCAGUGGCAAGAAUUAAAAAAGGAAUAAACUAUGUGCUUCUUAAAAUACUAUGCAAAACACAAAAUGUCCCAAAGGACACAAUGGACCAUGUAAAUGAGGUAUAUGUUAAAGAAGAUAUUUCUGACCAUACCCUUUCUGAAUUGAGCAACACCCAAGAUUUUCUCAAAGAUAAGGAAAAAAGCAGUGGCACAGAGAAAAACGCUACUGAAAAUGAGAGCCAAUCACUUAUCCCCAGUCCUAGUGUCUCAGAAACUGUACCAAUUGCUUCAGGAGAAUCUGAUAUAGAAAAUCUGGAUAAUAAGGAGAUUCAGAGUAAGUCUGGUGAUGGAGGCAGCAAAGAGAAAAUAAAGCAAUCUAGCUCAUCUGAAUGCAGUACUGUUGAUAUUGCUAUCUCUGAAGAAGAAGAAAUGUUCUAUGGAGGUGAAAGAUCAAAGCAUCUGAAAAAUGGUUGCAGACGCGGAUCUUCACUUGGUCAAAUCAGUGGAGCAUCCAAGAAAGGAAAAAUCUGGCAGAACAUCAGGAAAACCUGCUGCAAGAUUGUAGAGAACAAUUGGUUUAAGUGUUUUAUUGGGCUUGUUACUCUGCUCAGCACUGGCACUCUGGCUUUUGAAGAUAUAUAUAUGGAUCAGAGAAAGACAAUUAAAAUUUUAUUAGAAUAUGCUGACAUGAUCUUUACUUAUAUCUUCAUUCUGGAAAUGCUUCUAAAAUGGAUGGCAUAUGGUUUUAAGGCCUAUUUCUCUAAUGGCUGGUACAGGCUGGACUUCGUGGUUGUUAUUGUGUUUUGUCUUAGCUUAAUAGGCAAAACUCGGGAAGAACUAAAACCUCUUAUUUCCAUGAAAUUCCUUCGGCCCCUCAGAGUUCUAUCUCAAUUUGAAAGAAUGAAGGUGGUUGUGAGAGCUUUGAUCAAAACAACCUUACCCACUUUGAAUGUGUUUCUUGUCUGCCUGAUGAUCUGGCUGAUUUUUAGUAUCAUGGGAGUAGACUUAUUUGCUGGCAGAUUCUAUGAAUGCAUUGACCCAACAAGUGGAGAAAGGUUUCCUUCAUCUGAAGUCAUGAAUAAGAGUCGGUGUGAAAGCCUUCUGUUUAACGAAUCCAUGCUAUGGGAAAAUGCAAAAAUGAACUUUGAUAAUGUUGGAAAUGGUUUCCUUUCUCUGCUUCAAGUAGCAACAUUUAAUGGAUGGAUCACUAUUAUGAAUUCAGCAAUUGAUUCUGUUGCUGUUAAUAUACAGCCUCAUUUUGAAGUCAACAUCUACAUGUAUUGUUACUUUAUCAACUUUAUUAUAUUUGGAGUAUUUCUCCCUCUGAGUAUGCUGAUUACUGUUAUUAUUGAUAAUUUCAACAAGCAUAAAAUAAAGCUGGGAGGCUCAAAUAUCUUUAUAACGGUUAAACAGAGAAAACAGUACCGCAGGCUGAAGAAGCUAAUGUAUGAGGAUUCUCAAAGACCAGUACCUCGCCCAUUAAACAAGCUCCAAGGAUUCAUCUUUGAUGUGGUAACAAGCCAAGCUUUUAAUGUCAUUGUUAUGGUUCUUAUAUGUUUCCAAGCAAUAGCCAUGAUGAUAGACACUGAUGUUCAGAGUCUACAAAUGUCCAUUGCUCUCUACUGGAUUAACUCAAUUUUUGUUAUGCUAUAUACUAUGGAAUGUAUACUGAAGCUCAUCGCUUUCCGUUGUUUUUAUUUCACCAUUGCGUGGAACAUUUUUGAUUUUAUGGUGGUUAUUUUCUCCAUCACAGGACUAUGUCUGCCUAUGACAGUAGGAUCCUACCUUGUGCCUCCUUCACUUGUGCAACUGAUACUUCUCUCACGGAUCAUUCACAUGCUGCGUCUUGGAAAAGGACCAAAGGUGUUUCAUAAUCUGAUGCUUCCUUUGAUGCUGUCCCUCCCAGCAUUAUUGAACAUCAUUCUUCUCAUCUUCCUGGUCAUGUUCAUCUAUGCCGUAUUUGGAAUGUAUAAUUUUGCCUAUGUUAAAAAAGAAGCUGGAAUUAAUGAUGUGUCUAAUUUUGAAACCUUUGGCAACAGUAUGCUCUGUCUUUUUCAAGUUGCAAUAUUUGCUGGUUGGGAUGGGAUGCUUGAUGCAAUUUUCAACAGUAAAUGGUCUGACUGUGAUCCUGAUAAAAUUAACCCUGGGACUCAAGUUAGAGGAGAUUGUGGGAACCCCUCUGUUGGGAUUUUUUAUUUUGUCAGUUAUAUCCUCAUAUCAUGGCUGAUCAUUGUAAAUAUGUACAUUGUUGUUGUCAUGGAGUUUUUAAAUAUUGCUUCUAAGAAGAAAAACAAGACCUUGAGUGAAGAUGAUUUUAGGAAAUUCUUUCAGGUAUGGAAAAGGUUUGAUCCUGAUAGGACCCAGUACAUAGACUCUAGCAAGCUUUCAGAUUUUGCAGCUGCUCUUGAUCCUCCUCUUUUCAUGGCAAAACCAAACAAGGGCCAGCUCAUUGCUUUGGACCUCCCCAUGGCUGUUGGGGACAGAAUUCAUUGCCUCGAUAUCUUACUUGCUUUUACAAAGAGAGUUAUGGGUCAAGAUGUGAGGAUGGAGAAAGUUGUUUCAGAAAUAGAAUCAGGGUUUUUGUUAGCCAACCCUUUUAAGAUCACAUGUGAGCCAAUUACGACUACUUUGAAACGAAAACAAGAGGCAGUUUCAGCAACCAUCAUUCAACGUGCUUAUAAAAAUUACCGCUUGAGGCGAAAUGACAAAAAUACAUCAGAUAUUCAUAUGAUAGAUGGUGACAGAGAUGUUCAUGCUACUAAAGAAGGUGCCUAUUUUGACAAAGCUAAGGAAAAGUCACCUAUUCAAAGCCAGAUCUAAUACCACUUACCACCUCUUUUCAUAUUUCUUCACAUAUCUGAAAAAUGUUGAAAGCCUAAGCCAGGAAUAAAAGAAAAGUAGAGAUAAUAAUCAGUUCUUUACAACCGAUGGUAAUUAAGCUUGUAUUCACAAGACUUCAUGCCAAAUUCACUUUUUAGCAUUAUAUCUAACAAAUCAAGAGAAUCCUUAAUAUUGCUGCAGUGAGUUUAAAGUGGGUUAAAGUGGCCAUUUGACAAUCUCAUAUUUGUUUUCUCUACAUGGCUUAUAUGAUGUGUGCCUUCUAGGGAAUGAAGGGAAGUGGUGAUAGAGAUCAGCAGCAGCAGGGGCUUUCUUUUAUAUUUUAUGUAUAAUUUAAUGGGCUUUAAGUCACCACUAUUAAGACUUACAAAUAAGCAAAUACUUUCCUGAUGUGGGAUGGUGAAAUGCUAAUGGCCAUUAAAUCAUAAACUUGCCUAGACAAAAGCCAAUUGGAAGAAGGGAGAGAGCAGUUCUUUAGAAAGUGCCUUUGAGAUCAACCUCAGAGAUUCUUGGGCUGAUUAAAACUGCAUUUGAAAAAGAUUGGUUGAAGCUCUGUGUUUAUUUUUGUAUGUUCUUGUUUUCAUUUGGAACUGGGAAUGAAUAGGAUUUCAUUGUGCUCAAGCUCCUGGUUUCUCAUCUCUGGAUAGUUUCACCUAAGCUCUGGCUCUUAAGCAGGACAGAUUCGUAAAACAAGAAGCAUAAAGGAGAGGUAUAGCCUUUUUUUUUUUUUUUUUUUUCAUUUUCUUCUCAUUUACACCUAUUUUUUUAAAAAGUAUACAUUUACUAAAAUGAUGUAAUAAAUAACAUGUUAAUAGACUCAAGCUUUACCUUAUGAAAUUGAUGUAUUUUUACCAGUUAUUUCUAAUGUAACAUUGAAUAUAUAAGAUCUGACAAAUGUAUGUUUAAACAUGAAUUAGAAGAGUUGAGAACUACCAUUAUGUAUAGGGAUUCUCAUAGUGUCUUGGCCCUUAAUUGGAAAGUUGUGGCAACUUUAAAGUACUUUUUACUGUAUGUUAUAAUUCUUUAUAACUUAGAGAGAGACAAUGGUCACUCAAACUAUGAGAACUAUGAAUUAGGAGAUAAAAGUUUAAAUUUGUUGUUGUUUUAUAACAGUAUGUACAAGUUAGUUUUCCCUUAUAUAUUUACGUUUUCAAGUUUUUUAAUCUCAUCAUAUACAUCCAUACUCUAUAAAAUGUUUUAUAUUCAAAGAACUGUAAAAUCCUAAACAUUAGUUUUCACUAUUGAAAUUGUUUUUUAAAGAUAGGCAUAAAUAGUUGUCCUUAGACUUAUUCAUACAAAUAUAGUCAUUUACUUCUAUGUAGUUUGAGAUUCUGAGAGUUAUUCCAACUUUAUGAAGAUUGAUUUCAAUGUGCCUGCUAAGUCCUAAAAGAUUCAGAAAGAAAAUUUAUAUAUUAUUGAUUUAAAUAUCAUCCUUUAAAUAUGUUGUAUAACAUUCAAUAUAGUUUAUGUAUCAGUGAUUGUAUUUUAUUCUGAAUGCAUGAUCUCAAGCCUUAACUACUAUAAUCUUUUUCUGCCCCUCAGAAAUUGAAUAACCUAACCAAGAUGCCUUUAGGGGAUGCCCUAAGUAAAUGUAAUUUCAGAUUUCAGGGUUUUUUUUUUUUCCUCUCUAAGUGUUCCUUCCCUUUCUUCUCCUGCUCUCCAUCAUGUUAUGGAGACCAGUGAGGAACCAGUGUUAACUUGGUGACAAUGUGACAGCUGGUGCUUUAUCUAAGCUCCGUUUUCUAUUUCUUGGGAAUGCUUUAUUGUGGAAACUGCUUCAGAUACUUAAAUUGAAUCAUAACUUGCUUCUGUAAAUUGCGUAAAGACAACAAACUGAUUUUAGUUUGAAAAGUUUAUCUUUUACUUGUAAACCUUGUUUGCCAGUUACCUUCCGAAAGCUGUGUAAAGAGUUAUUUUUAACAAAGUCUUAACAAUAUAUGUUACUUUUUAGAUACUAUAGAAAAUAAUAAAUAUAACCUGUAAACCACA